GCUUCUCUUUUCCUUGGCGGAGGAGGGAGACCACAGAGCCCUGGGUUGUGGAAGAGGUGGCUGUUCCCUGUCAUCAGUAUGCAGCGAUUGCUCUUUCCGCCGUUGAGGGCCUUGAAGGGGAGGCAGUAUCUGCCGCUCCUGGCUCCUAGGGCAGCGCCUAGAGCACAGUGUGAUUGCAUCAGGCGCCCUUUGAGGCCAGGGCAAUACAGCACCAUCUCUGAAGUAGCUUUGCAAUCUGGAAGGGGUACAGUGUCCCUUCCCUCAAAGGCUGCUGAGCGGGUGGUGGGCCGAUGGCUCCUGGUCUGCAGUGGAACAGUGGCUGGAGCAGUUAUUCUUGGUGGAGUAACUAGGUUGACAGAGUCUGGCCUCUCGAUGGUAGAUUGGCAUUUAAUAAAGGAGAUGAAGCCACCUACAAGCCAAGAGGAAUGGGAAGCAGAAUUCCAAAGAUACCAGCAAUUUCCAGAAUUUAAAAUCUUGAAUCAUGAUAUGACACUGACAGAAUUCAAGUUCAUCUGGUACAUGGAGUACUCACACCGAAUGUGGGGUCGCCUUGUAGGCCUUGUGUACAUCCUGCCUGCUGCCUACUUUUGGAGAAAGGGCUGGCUCAGCCGUGGCAUGAAAGGACGUGUUCUUGCCCUCUGUGGCCUCGUCUGCUUCCAGGGUCUGUUGGGAUGGUAUAUGGUGAAAAGUGGACUAGAAGAAAAAUCAGACUCCCAUGACAUCCCUCGGGUCAGUCAGUACCGCCUUGCUGCCCACCUGGGAUCAGCCCUGGUUCUUUAUUGUGCCAGCUUGUGGACCUCACUGUCACUGCUACUCCCUCCGCACAAGUUGCCUGAAACCCACCAACUCCUACAGUUGAGACGAUUUGCUCAUGGAACAGCAGGUCUGGUGUUCCUUACGGCCCUCUCAGGGGCUUUUGUGGCAGGGCUAGAUGCUGGGCUUGUUUAUAACUCCUUUCCCAAAAUGGGAGAAUCCUGGAUCCCGGAGGACCUCUUUACCUUCUCCCCCAUCCUGAGGAAUGUUUUUGAGAAUCCCACCAUGGUGCAGUUUGAUCACCGGAUUCUGACUCUUUCUUCCCUGCAGGGAAUCACUUCAGUCACUGCCAUUACAGUGCUCUACUUCCUCUCUCGGAGAAUUCCCCUUCCUAGAAGGACCAAGAUGGCAGCAGUGACUCUGCUGGCUUUGGCGUAUACACAGGUGGGCUUGGGCAUCAGCACGCUGCUGAUGUAUGUCCCAACUCCUCUGGCCGCCACUCACCAGUCAGGCUCCUUGGCUUUGCUCACUGGUGCUCUUUGGCUGAUGAAUGAACUCCGAAGAGUCCCAAAAUGAUUCUUAGAGGACCAGCCUCCUGGGACUGUGACUGCUUUUGAGAGCUCUUCAGAGAUCAUAAGAACUUGGGCUUUUCUACGAGAUGACCUUGACAUACCAAGUGGUUUCCAAAUGGUCAACUUACUUAAAAAUCUUUUCCUGUUUUGAGAUAGUCACUGGAUCAAGAAUGCAUUAAGUGUGGUUACCCUAAAUGUUCCCUUUUAAAUCUGCUUUUCAUGUUGAAAAUCAGUUUUAAUGUAGAGAAAGAAAUGUCUGCCAUUUGCUGCUUAACAGGCUUUGUGUCAGGUUUUUCAGUGUUGGCAAGCUCUUGGUUCUACGUGGAUGAUUUCUACGUGGAUGUUCUCCUGAGUCCUUAAUUCUGCCUAAAUAGAAUUUCUUUAUGAUCUUAACUUCACUUCCAUUAGGUGAAGAUUGAAAGGAUAGGAUUGACAUACCCAAAGUAGCCAGCUGGUCUUCAGCAAAAAAAAAAAAGCUAAUGUCUUCUAAUAUCCUGAUUUUCAGAAAUGGGGAAAUUGCAGAUUUUGACAAGCUUAAUGUGUAUAUGUAGCAAAAUGGUUUUUAAGUACUUGGAAAAGGAGGUAAUCGCCAAAUAGUUCCAUUUUUUUUUUUUUUUUUGAGACAGAGUUUCACUCUUGUUGCCCAGGCUGGAGUACAAUGGCGUGAUCUCAGCUCACUCUGCAACCUCCACUUCCCAGGUUCAAGCGAUUCUCAUGCCUCAGCCUCCCGAGUAGCUGGGACUACAGGCACAAGUCACCAUGCCUGGCUAAUUUUGUAUUUUUAGUAGAGAAGGGGUUUCACCACAUUGGCCGGGCUGGUCUUGAACUCCUGACCUCAGGUAAUCCGCCCAUCUCGGCUUCCCAAAGUGCUGAGAUUACAGGCAUGGGCCACCACGCCCAGCUAGUUCCUCUUUUGAUAAGGCUGUUAACAUUACAAGGUCAGAGAGAGGAAUGGAAUCGACAGUAUAAAUUGGUUCCUGAGAGGGUUUCCUAACAGCUUUGUAAUAAGAAAAAUAUGGCCUUGAUGGUGUAGUGCAUGGACAUCUACCCAGAUAAACAAAUUGUUGACUGCUGAAUUAAUGUGAUUUUGGUCUCUAUUGAUAUUUCAUAGGGCCCUGUCUUAUUCAACUUUACUUUUAAAAUCAGUGAUUUGGAUGAAGGCAUCAGAAACAUCUGAUUUGAGGAUGGAGCAACCCAAUAUUGCUAAUAUAAUAGAUGACAGUGGCAACUGAAAACAGUCCCAGAAUGACCCCAUCGAGAUGAAAUUAAACAGAUUAGAAAUGUAACAUACUCAUUUAAAUUAAAUAAGUUGUAUAAGUUUGGGCUGAAGAAACCUGGCCUUAUAUCAUUUCAUAUAAAAAAGACGGGAUUUUAGUUGUCCUCAGGUUCAAUAUGAACCAAGUAGUAUUCAUGUUGUUAUUAUAUGAUAACAGAAAAAUUAGUGGUACUUCAGGUUUUAUCAGUAGAAGUGUCACAGCCAUAGUCAAAAUACCCCUAACAUACUGCAUUUCACUCUGGGUACCAAAUUUAAGCAAGAUAUUGAUGGCCACUAAGUGUGUAUCCAGAAGAAGAGAUCAGAAUGAUGAGUCCAGAACCCCUGUCACACAGGGAAUAGGUGAAGGAACUAGGGAUAUUUAACUGGAGCAGAGAACAUCUGGAGAGAGAGCAAGAUUCCUGUCCUUGAGAAGUUGAAGCCGUCUCAUGCAGAAGAGGGAAUGAGCUUCCAUUAUGCUGCAGAGCUGGCAGCAAUGGAUGAAAGUUGCAGGAAGUUAGUUUUAGUUCUGUAGAAGGCAAGAGUAGGGUAGACCAAAUCAAAUGCUCACUGGGGUCAGGCUGAUGGAGACAGUAACACUGGCGAGCAGGUGCCCCAGCUCGGACUAUACUGCUGAGUUCUGGUCUGUUGCUGCCACUCUACAGGUCCAGGGUUGUUAGAUCUUCUGGGUUUUUGUUUUGCUUUUUGAAAUAAGGAAAAUAAGCUUAUCUUAAGUUUAUUUUUCCUUGGAUAUACCUAGAUUCCAUACAGUGACAAUACAAAUACAAAGGAAGAACAUCUGGAUUUCAUCCUUGACCUCAUUUACAAAGCAAAAAGAGAUGCUGGAUUCAGAUAUAAAUGUUUAAUUUUGCAGUGUUUAAGUCAGCAAAUCUUCUGUUUUUUAAAAAUAAGCCACAUAUCUAGAUUUUUCUGUGAAAGCUCUCAAUUAAGUGUUGGGAACUAAUUUCAAGAUUUUAAAAAAUGUUAUGCAGGCUUAACGUGUCUGAGAGCCAUAAAUGACCUAACGUUUCCCGUUAGUCUCUGAACUAGGUGAUCUCAGUUCUCUUUCAACUCCAGUACUCUGUAAGUUUCUGUGACCUGUAGUGUACCAUUCUCAGGUGGUGAUAUGGUUUGGAUGUUUUGUCCCCUCCAAAUCUCAUGUUCAAAGUGUGACAUUCAGUGUUAGAGGUGGGCCUAGUAGGAGGUAUUUGGGUCAUGGGGGCGGAUCCCUUAUGUAUGACUUUGUGCCAUCCCCAUAGUAAUGAGUGAGUUCUCACUCUGGUUGUUUAUGCAAGAGCUGGUUGUUUAAAAGAGCCUGGAACUUCCUCCUCUCUCGCUUGCUCUCUCUCACCAUGUGACACACUGGCUCCCCUUCACCUUCUGCCAUGAUUGUAAGCUUCGUGAGGCCCUCACCAGAAGCAGAUGCCAGCGCCAUGCUUCCUAUACAGUUCUAUGCAGAACAGUGAGCCAAAUAAACCUCUUUUCUUUCUAAAAAUUGUCAGUAUUUCCUUAUAGCAAUGCAAGCCGACUAACACAGGUGAUUCUUAGCAAAACAGUUUGUCAAUUUUUCAUAAAUGCUGGACCCUGGCUGGGCUUAUGCUAUUGCCUAGAAGAGAUUCCCAACUUCUCUCUUAUUUGAAUCUUAGAAAAAUCCCAAAGCCCAAGCCUCAUCUAAGACCAAUUAAGUCACAAUCCCUGGAGGAAGUAAAAGGCAUAUUUUUAAAGUUCCCCAGGUGAUUCCAAUGUGCAGACAAGUCUAGGGACCACUGGCUUAGGUCCUAAUAGCCUAGUUACCUUAGAAAGUUCUGACUAGCUUAUUCCCAUUCCCUUCUAAUUUCCACCCCACCUUAUCAUUUGAUCUGCUAUGUUGCUCCUAUUAGUAUGUUAGUAGGAUAUGGUCUCUUCUGGAUAGAAUCCUUCAAAGAAAGGGAACUGUAGUUCCUGAGGCAGGUUCCCACACCAUCCUCUCCUGAUCCUCAAACCCAGGUUGUCCUUAGUUAGUAACUGAGUCAGCAGAGGGCAGUAUGACCCAACCCAAAGAACCAUAUAUUAAUGCUUCUACAGUUGCCUCCAAGGAAGUAGCAACUCAUGAGUAAGUUAAGGUUUCAGAUGUUUUACUUCAUUUUUCUUUUAUUACAGAUGAUGAGUACAUUUGGAAAAACAACUGGUUGCAUUUAGCUAUAUAACUGUAUUAUAUCUAUGAGCUUCUGGUGAAUGAUUAUCUUAGGGUUUUUUUUGUAUUUAUGUUAUUCCCAGCACUCCCAGACACAUAUCAAAUAUUGAAUUAGUGAAUGCAUGAAUGGAAAAUGGAUAAUUACAGAUUGAUGUUCCAAAUACCUUUUUCCAAAAAAACAAGUCAUCACAUACCUAUAGGAUUAAAUAGAUUUCCCUUAAUAUUUUCAAAGGUCUCUCUGCACUUACGUCCAUUGUUUUUAAAACAUGAAGGAAAUUAAAACACAUGGCUUUCUUAA